AGAAUUCUCGCAGGCGCCUGGGCCGGGUGCCCGGCCGUGCCAUCCUGUCCGGGGUCCCCGGCCCAUGUGGCCUUUCUUCCAGCGACAGUACACUUAGCUCAGAACGGAUUGACACCCACUCUGUGUUUCCACCGGGCGCGCAGGCUCUGCAAUGCGGAGCGCGUUCUCUGAAGGACAGGCCCCGGAGUCACGGCUACAGCCACAGAAAGCGGAAACCGAGCUGCAGUCCAGAGGGGAUCCCCGUACAUUUCCAGCGGGCUCAGACACAGGGUCCCCCACAAGAAAGAAACAGGACAGAAAAAGUCAGGACACGUAUGCUGUGGAGAGUCGAGGUCUCGCCUAGAUCUUGGGUGUGGGUAGACGCAGCCGCUGGCAGUUUUCCUUUCCAGCGUCUCUGGGGAGCCUGGAGAUGUCCUUGGUGCCGAUGUGACACGAAGAGUGAUUGCGCCGCCCUGCAGAGGCGGUGGCGGGACGCUGCGCUCGGGCUGGGAAAGGCCGGCCCCAGGGCGACCCCUCCGGAGGCCCCCGGAGAGCAGGUCAUUUGAUUGCCCGCCUCAGAACGAUGGAUCUGCAUCUCUUCGACUACUCAGAGCCAGGGAACUUCUCGGACAUCAGCUGGCCAUGCAACAGCAGCGACUGCAUCGUGGUGGACACGGUGAUGUGUCCCAACAUGCCCAACAAAAGCGUCCUGCUCUACACGCUCUCCUUCAUUUACAUUUUCAUCUUCGUCAUCGGCAUGAUUGCCAACUCCGUGGUGGUCUGGGUGAAUAUCCAGGCCAAGACCACAGGCUAUGACACGCACUGCUACAUCUUGAACCUGGCCAUUGCCGACCUGUGGGUUGUCCUCACCAUCCCAGUCUGGGUGGUCAGUCUCGUGCAGCACAACCAGUGGCCCAUGGGCGAGCUCACGUGCAAAGUCACACACCUCAUCUUCUCCAUCAACCUCUUCGGCAGCAUUUUCUUCCUCACGUGCAUGAGCGUGGACCGCUACCUCUCCAUCACCUACUUCACCAACACCCCCAGCAGCAGGAAGAAGAUGGUACGCCGUGUCGUCUGCAUCCUGGUGUGGCUGCUGGCCUUCUGCGUGUCUCUGCCUGACACCUACUACCUGAAGACCGUCACGUCUGCGUCCAACAAUGAGACCUACUGCCGGUCCUUCUACCCCGAGCACAGCAUCAAGGAGUGGCUGAUCGGCAUGGAGCUGGUCUCCGUUGUCUUGGGCUUUGCCGUUCCCUUCUCCAUUAUCGCUGUCUUCUACUUCCUGCUGGCCAGAGCCAUCUCGGCGUCCAGUGACCAGGAGAAGCACAGCAGCCGGAAGAUCAUCUUCUCCUACGUGGUGGUCUUCCUUGUCUGCUGGCUGCCCUACCACGUGGCGGUGCUGCUGGACAUCUUCUCCAUCCUGCACUACAUCCCUUUCACCUGCCGGCUGGAGCACGCCCUCUUCACGGCCCUGCAUGUCACACAGUGCCUGUCGCUGGUGCACUGCUGCGUCAACCCUGUCCUCUACAGCUUCAUCAAUCGCAACUACAGGUACGAGCUGAUGAAGGCCUUCAUCUUCAAGUACUCGGCCAAAACAGGGCUCACCAAGCUCAUCGAUGCCUCCAGAGUCUCAGAGACGGAGUACUCUGCCUUGGAGCAGAGCACCAAAUGAUCUGCCCUGGAGAGGCUCUGGGACGGGUUUACUUGUUUUUGAACAGGGUGAUGGGCCCUAUGGUUUUCUAGAGCAAAGCAAAGUAGCUUCGGGUCUUGAUGCUUGAGUAGAGUGAAGAGGGGAGCACGUGCCCCCUGCAUCCAUUCUCUCUUUCUCUUGAUGACGCAGCUGUCAUUUGGCUGUGCGUGCUGACAGUUUUGCAACAGGCAGAGCUGUGUCGCACAGCAGUGCUGUGCGUCAGAGCCAGCUGAGGACAGGCUUGCCUGGACUUCUGUAAGAUAGGAUUUUCUGUGUUUCCUGAAUUUUUUAUAUGGUGAUUUGUAUUUAAAUUUUAAGACUUUAUUUUCUCACUAUUGGUGUACCUUAUAAAUGUAUUUGAAAGUUAAAUAUAUUUUAAAUAUUGUUUGGGAGGCAUAGUGCUGACAUAUAUUCAGAGUGUUGUAGUUUUAAGGUUAGCGUGACUUCAGUUUUGACUAAGGAUGACACUAAUUGUUAGCUGUUUUGAAAUUAUAUAUAUAUAAAUAUAUAUAAAUAUAUAAAUAUAUGCCAGUCUUGGCUGAAAUGUUUUAUUUACCAUAGUUUUAUAUCUGUGUGGUGUUUUGUACCGGCACGGGAUAUGGAACGAAAACUGCUUUGUAAUGCAGUUUGUGACAUUAAUAGUAUUGUAAAGUUACAUUUUAAAAUAAACAAAAAACUGUUCUGGACUGCAAAUCUGCACACACAACGAACAGUUGCAUUUCAGAGAGUUCUCUCAAUUUGUAAGUUAUUUUUUUUUAAUAAAGAUUUUUGUUUCCUAAAAA